ACAUUUGUGAUCACCUGGUCACACACCUGGGCAGGAGGCUGCCCCUCCCUGGUUUGAGGAAGCAGGAAAAGGUACCCGCGAGAGACAGCCAGCAGUUCUGUGGAGCAGCGGUGGCCGGCUAGGAUGGGCUGUCUCUGGGGUCUGGCUCUGCCCCUUUUCUUCUUCUGCUGGGAGGUUGGGGUCUCUGGGAGCUCUGCAGGCCCCAGCACCCGCAGAGCAGACACUGCGAUGACAACGGACGACACAGAAGUGCCCGCUAUGACUCUAGCACCGGGCCACGCCGCUCUGGAAACUCAAACACUGAGCGCUGAGACCUCUUCUAGGGCCUCAACCCCAGCCGGCCCCGUUCCAGAAGCAGAGACCAGGGGAUCCAAGAGAAUUUCCCCUGCAAGAGAGACCAGGAGUUUCACAAAAACAUCUCCCAACUUCAUGGUGCUGAUCGCCACCUCCGUGGAGACAUCAGCCGCCAGUGGCAGCCCCGAGGGAGCUGGAAUGACCACAGUUCAGACCAUCACAGGCAGUGAUCCCGAGGAAGCCAUCUUUGACACCCUUUGCACCGAUGACAGCUCUGAAGAGGCAAAGACACUCACAAUGGACAUAUUGACAUUGGCUCACACCUCCACAGAAGCUAAGGGCCUGUCCUCAGAGAGCAGUGCCUCUUCCGACGGCCCCCAUCCAGUCAUCACCCCGUCACGGGCCUCAGAGAGCAGCGCCUCUUCCGACGGCCCCCAUCCAGUCAUCACCCCGUCACGGGCCUCAGAGAGCAGCGCCUCUUCCGACGGCCCCCAUCCAGUCAUCACCCCGUCACGGGCCUCAGAGAGCAGCGCCUCUUCCGACGGCCCCCAUCCAGUCAUCACCCCCUCAUGGUCCCCGGGAUCUGACGUCACUCUCCUCGCUGAAGCCCUGGUGACUGUCACAAACAUCGAGGUUAUUAAUUGCAGCAUCACAGAAAUAGAAACAACGACUUCCAGCAUCCCUGGGGCCUCAGACACAGAUCCCAUCCCCACGGAAGGGGUGAAGGCCUCGUCCACCUCCGAUCCACCAGCUCUGCCUGACUCCACUGAAGCAAAACCACACAUCACUGAGGUCACAGCCUCUGCCGAGACCCUGUCCACAGCCGGCACCACAGAGUCAGCUGCACCUGAUGCCACGAUUGGGACCCCACUCCCCACCAACAGCACCAUAGAAAGAGAAGUGACAGCACCCGGGGCCACGACCCUCAGUGGAGCUCUGGCCACAGGGAAUCCCCUGGAAGAAACCUCAGCCCUCUCUGUUGAGACACCAAGUUACGUCAAAGUCUCAGGAGCAGCUCCGGUCUCCAUAGAGGCUGGGUCAGCAGUGGGCAAAACAACUUCCUUUGCUGGGAGCUCUGCUUCCUCCUACAGCCCCUCGGAAGCCGCCCUCAAGAACUUCACCCCUUCAGAGACACUGACCACGGACAUCGCAACCAAGGGGCCCUUCCCCACCAGCAGGGACCCUCUUCCUUCUGUCCCUCCAACUACAACCAACAGCAGCCGAGGGACGAACAGCACCUUAGCCAAGAUCACAACCUCAGCGAAGACCACGAUGAAGCCCCCAACAGCCACGCCCACGACUGCCCGGACGAGGCCGACCACAGACAUGAGUGCAGGUGAAAAUGGAGGUUUCCUCCUCCUGCGGCUGAGUGUGGCUUCCCCGGAAGACCUCACUGACCCCAGAGUGGCAGAAAGGCUGAUGCAGCAGCUCCACCGGGAACUCCACGCCCACGCGCCUCACUUCCAGGUCUCCUUACUGCGUGUCAGGAGAGGCUAACGGACAUCAGCUGCAGCCAGGCAUGUCCCGUAUGCCAAAAGAGGGUGCUGCCCCUAGCCUGGGCCCCCACCGACAGACUGCAGCUGCGUUACUGUGCUGAGAGGUACCCAGAAGGUUCCCAUGAAGGGCAGCAUGUCCAAGCCCCUGACCCCAGAUGUGGCAACAGGACCCUCGCUCACAUCCACCGGAGUGUAUGUGUGGGGAGGGGCUUCACCUGUUCCCAGAGGUGUCCUUGGACUCACCUUGGCACAUGUUCUGUGUUUCAGUAAAGAGAGACCUGAUCACCCAUCUGUGUGCUUCCAUCCUGCAUUAAAAUUCACUCAGUGUGGCCCAGA